AGACUACCCGGGCCCUCACAGAAGGCGGUGGCGGGCGGGUGCAGCGAGUUUGUCCCCUUGCCCGCACACUGCUUGGCCUCUGUACUUAAGUGCGGUGGCCGCCUGCCUCGCUGGAGCUUCUCUGCCGCAGCCAUCCGUGCUGCUUGGGACGGGCCGGGGCGCGAAGGCGGUCGCAUCCAUCGCUCUGCCCUCCUGCUUCUCUUGUGUAAUCAGCUGCCUAUUUGGAAAUUGGGCAGGGUUUGCGACUGGAUGCUAAUGUCACUGACUAGUUUUCAGCCUACCAUCCAGAAGUAACAUGUUCCCAGCUUUGGAAACGCACCUAAAGCAGACUAUUCCUGAUCCUUAUGAAGACUUUAUGUACCGUCACCUCCAAUAUUAUGGCUACUUUAAAGCUCAGAGAGGCAGUUUACCAAACUCUGCUACGCAUCAGCAUGUUCGGAAGAAUAACCCUCAAUGCCUGUUGAAUGGCUCUCUUGGGGAAAAAGAUGAUUUGAUACCAGACACCCUGCAAAAGGAGAAGCUUCUAUGGCCUAUCAGUUUAUCUUCAGCUGUGCACAGACAGAUAGAAGCCAUCAACAGAGACUUUCACUCUUGCCUGGGCUGGAUGCAGUGGCGCGGCCUCAGCUCACUGCAACCUCCACCUCCCAGAUUCAAGGAUUCUCCUGCCUCAGCUUUCCGAGUAGCUGGGAUUACAGAUUCACAUAUGCUGAGUUUACCACAUCUUAGGAGCAGACAGCUUCUUUAUGAUGAGUUGGAUGAAGUAAACCCACGUCUUCGAGAACCCCAAGAGCUCUUUUCCAUUUUGUCUACCAAGAGGCCACUGCAGGCUCCAAGAUGGCCAAUUGAAUGUGAGGUCAUCAAGGAAAACAUCCAUCAUAUUGAGUGGGCUCCACCUCAACCAGAAUAUUUCUAUCAGCCUAAAGGAAAUGAAAAGGUACCAGAGAUUGUAGGAGAGAAAAAAGGAACAGUUGUCUAUCAAUUAGAUUCAGUGCCUAUAGAAGGUUCCUAUUUUACCAGUUCCAGAGUGGGAGGCAAACGAGGAAUUGUCAAGGAACUUGCUGUCACGUUGCAAGGACCAGAAGAUAAUACUCUACUGUUUGAAUCAAGGUUUGAGAGUGGGAAUCUGCAAAAAGCUGUCAGAGUAGACACCUAUGAGUAUGAACUCACCUUGCGAACUGACCUCUACACUAACAAACACACUCAGUGGUUUUAUUUUCGUGUUCAGAACACCAGAAAAGAUGCUACCUAUCGCUUCACCAUUGUCAACUUGCUAAAACCCAAGAGUCUUUAUACUGUAGGGAUGAAGCCACUCUUGUACUCCCAAUUGGAUGCCAACACCCGCAAUAUUGGCUGGAGGAGAGAAGGAAAUGAAAUCAAGUACUACAAGAACAACACGGAUGAUGGGCAGCAGCCCUUCUACUGUCUCACGUGGACCAUUCAGUUUCCAUAUGACCAGGACACUUGCUUCUUUGCACACUUCUACCCAUAUACAUACACUGAUUUGCAAUGCUACCUCCUGUCAGUGGCAAACAACCCUAUCCAGUCUCAGUUCUGCAAGCUCCAAACUUUAUGCAGGAGCCUAGCAGGAAAUACCGUUUACUUGCUCACCAUCACCAACCCAUCCCAGACCCCUCAAGAGGCAGCUGCAAAGAAAGCUGUGGUCUUGAGUGCCAGAGUUCACCCUGGAGAAAGUAAUGGCUCCUGGGUUAUGAAAGGCUUUUUGGACUUCAUCCUUAGCAACUCCCCAGAUGCCCAGCUCCUCAGAGAUAUUUUUGUCUUCAAGGUGCUUCCCAUGUUAAAUCCAGAUGGUGUGAUUGUGGGGAAUUAUCGGUGUUCCUUGGCCGGAAGGGAUUUGAACAGGCAUUAUAAAACCAUUCUGAAGGAGUCUUUCCCUUGUAUUUGGUACACCAGGAACAUGAUCAAAAGACUUCUUGAAGAAAGAGAGGUUCUGUUGUAUUGUGAUUUCCAUGGCCACAGUCGUAAGAAUAAUAUCUUCCUGUAUGGCUGUAAUAACAACAAUCGCAAAUACUGGCUUCAUGAACGAGUCUUUCCUUUAAUGUUAUGCAAAAAUGCACCAGAUAAGUUCUCUUUUCACAGUUGUAAUUUUAAGGUCCAAAAAUGCAAAGAAGGAACAGGACGAGUUGUUAUGUGGCGGAUGGGAAUCCUAAACAGCUACACCAUGGAGUCUACCUUUGGCGGGUCCACCCUGGGUAAUAAAAGAGACACCCACUUUACCAUCGAAGAUCUGAAGUCCUUAGGUUAUCAUGUCUGUGACACCCUUCUGGACUUUUGUGAUCCUGACCAAAUGAAGUUCACUCAGUGUCUAGCAGAGCUUAAGGAGCUUUUACGACAGGAAAUCCACAAGAAAUUCCAUGAACUUGGACAAGAUGUAGAUUUAGAAGGAAGUUGGAGUGACAUCUCUUUGUCUGACAUUGAAUCCAGCACCAGUGGCUCUGACAGUUCUCUCUCAGAUGGUCUUCCUGUUCACCUAGCAAACAUAGCAGAUGAGCUGACUCAGAAAAAGAAGAUGUUUAAGAAGAAAAAAAAGAAGUCACUUCAGACUAGGAAACAGCGAAAUGAGCAGUAUCAGAAAAAAAAUUUGAUGCAGAAGUUAAAGUUAACAGAAGAUACCUCAGAAAAGGCAGGAUUUGCUUCUACUCUGCAAAAGCAGCCAACCUUUUUCAAAAACUCAGAGAAUUCCAGUUUUUUACCAAUGAAAAAUGAAAACCCAAGGUUAAAUGAGACAAAUUUAAAUAGAAGAGACAAAGACACCCCCCUGGACCCAUCAAUGGCCACCCUGAUUCUGCCUAAGAAUAAAGGGAGAAUGCAGAAUAAGAAGCCAGGCUUUACAGUAUCAUGCUCUCCAAAGAGAACCAUAAACUCCAGCCAAGAGCCAGCUCCAGGUAUGAAGCCAAACUGGCCUAGGAGCAGAUAUCCUGCCACAAAGAGAGGCUGUGCUGCCAUGGCGGCAUACCCAUCCUUGCACAUAUACACAUACCCGUAGGUGAGCCUGGGCUGUGCCACACAAGCACUUCAUCGGGGGUUUUGAGAUUAGACACAUUUUAUAAUGGGGGAGAUGUAUGACUGGGAACUGCAUUUACUUGUGGUAUACUGUGUUGUGCACUCAUGCACUGACCUUACACUUUGUACUUACACUGUGGGCAUGUGGUCAAGAUGCAUACCUCAUGAAUUCAACUAUUUUUUCAUAAAAUGAAAUUUUAUUAUGAUGUGUAAAAAUGCUUUAUCAGAAACUGAAGUGUGUUCUCAUGGCACACUUCAUGGCAGCACAGAUAUACCUCAUUUUAACCAAUAGAUAUUCUCUCUAAAAUUAUGUGCAAAUCAAUUUUUAAAAAUCAAAAUCUAUGUUAAACACAUUUUGGCAGUGUGCUAUAAUAAAAAAAAGUGUUGUGUCAAAGCUUUCUAGUGACGGUCAGUCCUACUGCUGUAUGUCAGGUUUGCUCACAAUGAGGUAUUCCCACAUAGAAAUAACAAUGCAUGUAUUACCCAGAAUUUAAUGUUGCGUACCUUAUGUUCAAUGAGGUUUUGUAAUUUUUUUAGGCUGAUGAUUAAAAUUCUUUCUCUCUAA